GCAGAGCAUGCCGGGAGCCGCCGGCCGCCGGUGUCCGGACCGCUCGCCCCCGUUUGGACCCGACUUCGGUUCUUCUGGGGUGUUGAUGCUCCUAAAGCCCGAGAGCACGUGUCCAGACCCUAGCCUGUACGACGCUGACUCUGCCCGGUCCCAGAACCAAAGCCAUGCCGGGGUGUGGCCUCUGACCCCACGCGGAGGGGACCUCGCCUUGCGGGACCCCACCUGGAACCCGACCUCCCAGCCUCGCAGCCGGCCUGAGCCGCCAUGCGCGGGAAGUUGCUGCCGCUGGCCGGCCUCUACCUGGUGCAGGGCCUGCCCUACGGGCUCCAGUCCGGCCUCCUGCCAGUGCUGCUGCGUGCCGGCGGCCUCUCGCUGACGCGCGUGGGGCUGGCCAAGGUUCUGUACGCUCCGUGGCUGCUCAAGCUGGCUUGGGCCCCGCUGGUGGACGCGCAGGGCUCGGCGAGGGCCUGGGUGACGCGCAGCACGGCGGGCCUGGGCCUGGUGUGUGGGCUGCUUGCCGGGCUGCCCCCUCCUGGAGCUGGCCAGGCCGGGCUGCCCGCCGCUGUGGCGGGGUUGCUGCUGUUGUUGAACCUGGGUGCCGCCAUGCAGGAUGUGGCCCUGGACGCGCUGGCUGUGCAGCUGCUGGAGCCGGCCGAACUGGGGCCGGGCAAUACCGUGCAGGUGGUCGCGUACAAGCUGGGGGCCGCGCUAGCUGGGGGCGCGCUGCUGGCGCUGCUGCCCACCUUCUCGUGGCCGCAACUCUUUCUGCUCCUGGCUGCCACCUACUGGCUGGCCGCGGCCCUGGCCUGGGCUGCACCAGCCCUGCGGCGGCUCCCACAGCAGCCCCCUUCCGAGCAGCGUCCCCACACCGCGCACCUUCUGCGGGACGUGCUAGCCGUGCCGGGGACCGUGUGGACGGCAGGCUUUGUGCUCACCUACAAGCUGGGUGAGCAGGGUGCCAGCAGCCUGUUUCCUCUUCUCCUGCUGGACCACGGCGUUUCUGCUCCCGAGUUGGGACUGUGGAAUGGUGUGGGUGCUGUGGUCUGCUCCAUCGCUGGCUCCUCCCUGGGUGGGACCUUGCUGGCCAAGCACUGGAAACUGCUGCCUCUGUUGAGGUCGGUGCUGCGCUUCCGCCUCGGGGGCCUAGCCUGUCAGACUGCCUUGGUCUUCCACCUGGACACCCUGGGGGCCAGCAUGGACGCUGGCACAAUCUUGAGAGGGUCAGCCUUGCUGAGCCUAUGUCUGCAGCACUUCUUGGGAGGCCUGGUCACCACAGUCACCUUCACUGGGAUGAUGCGCUGCAGCCAGCUGGCCCCCAGGGCCCUGCAGGUGAGUAGAUGUAGCAGGGACACAAGAGAGACCACGGGGCUGGGGCUGUGUGGGCCUGACCUUGACCGUGACCCCCACCCCCCUCAGGCCACACACUACAGCCUUCUGGCCACGCUGGAGCUGCUGGGGAAGCUGCUGCUGGGCACUCUGGCCGGAGGCCUGGCUGAUGGGUUGGGGCCACAUCCCUGCUUCUUGCUCCUGCUCAUCCUCUCUGCCUUUCCCGUUCUGUACCUGGACCUAGCACCCAGCACCUUUCUCUGAGCUGAGUGGCUGGAGUGGUCAAUAAAGCCACAUGUGCCUGUGGCCCAGA